ACAUGGUCCUUGCUUUUUUGGAAUUUCUAAUCUAGUUAGGAAGUUAAGACAGAUUUAUAACUGUAAUAUCAAGUUGAAAGUAAUAUGUCGUACAAAAUUAAAGGUACACUUGGUAUUUGACUUGUGCAAAUUUGUUUUAAACAACCCACACUUUAAUAUAUAAUAUAUUGGCACUGUGGCCAUGUGGAGACAUUUAGUCAUCUAGUAAGGUUAACAAUUUGUAACCUUUCAAGUAUUCUUAGAUAUGUGCUUGACAGUUGAGGAGAGGCUGGGCACCACAUGGAGAACCAUAGUUGGCAGUGUGCAGUAUUUUCGCUAUUGCCCUUAACAAUUUAGUUCUGACUCCCAAAGUGAUUACUCCACUCAGCAAAACAAAAGCCCUGCAAUUAUUUGGAGUCACCCUUCUUAAAGAUCGUAGUUGUUACUCAGGCAAGCUUCAAGUGAUAUUUUACAAACAACCCAUAAUAUUGUGCCCGAGAGGAGUUCUGAGCCAUAUACUUUCUCCAUCUUAUUCCAUUUUCAUUGAUGACCUGUCACUUUCAAAGAUUGUAGCACCAACAGCAAGUGGUAUAUUUAAUCCAGCUCUAAUUAACUACACCUAUUGUAUGGUAAGUUUGAACUUUUACAUAAUUUGAAUUGUCACAUGAUGGUGCUUCCUGUUGGUGAAAAGUUCCACUUGGGGAAUUACCAUCCACUUUUGUACAGAGUUUGUGCUAUUAUUUGAAUAUUUUCUUGUAGUUAUCCAUGAAAUGGGUUCUGUAGUGCCCUGGAGCAGCCCAUUGGGAAUUGCUAGACAGCAGGUGGAGCUCUUGGUCUCUGGGUCUCCCAUUUUUCACCUGGGCCUUUGCUGGACUGGAGCAGCUGUGCUUUCUCUUGCUCUACACAUUUGGGCUCUGGUGUUGGAACUUAUUUGUUGGAGAAAUGUCUUCAGAGUCAGAAAAGGAUAAAGAGAGACUGAUUCAAGCUGCCAAAAUGUUCUUCUUUCAUGUACAAGAUCUUGCUUCUGUCAUAAACACACUGACUGAAUUGUUUAGCCGCAGUAUGAAUACUCAAAUCCUUUUGAUGGCUGUGAAAAACAAUAGUUACAUUAAGGAUUUUUUUGAGCAAAUGCUCAAAAUUUUUAAGGAGAUGCAAUCUGUAGUGGAUGCAAGACAUGACAAAAUUCAAAAGGAGUCUUUAUGUUCCAAGGUUGCAAUGGCCAUGUGCUCUGUGGUUCAGAAGAGUACCAAUGUAGAGGAGUUGCAUCAGUCAGCUAAAGAAGUAUUCAAAAGUGCCCAUACGCCAGUCAUCAUCUCUGUGCUAAACAGCAGUAACAUCCUUGGGAGUCUGGAAUCUUCUCUUUCACACUUGAUGAAAUUCCCCAUCAUGAAUCUUCAAUUAAGUGACUUCUAUACAGAAGACACCAAAGAGCAAUCAGAUGUCACCACAUCUGAGAGAACCAGAAGUCCUCCAGGUUCUUCCAAAACCACUAUGAUAGACACCUUGAAAAAACUGCAGGAUGUACUAAAAACUGAGGAUUCCAAAAAUCCCACAAAGUCAGCAGCAGAUUUGUUGGAACAAAUUGUCAAGGCUAUGGGACCAAUCUUAGAGAUCCUCCAAAAAGCGAUAAAGACUAUGGAAAUGAAUAUUUCUGUGUUUAAGAAAGCCAGUGACAAGUAGGGAUGCAACAGAAAUGUUCAUUUCUGUCAGAAAACUACUUAAAAUCUUAUGGUUUUUCAUAGUAGUUUCUAAGAUCUUUUGGUGCCAAACAUGUGCUAUGUUAGAACAUAAGUACACAAAAGUCAUCUGGCAAAACAUUUACCUGUAGUUUUGCUUUAUUAAAAUAAAAAGAAAUAAUUAAGAAAGCCUGUUUGAAAUGUCAGUCACUAAGAAGAAUAUAUUGUUGAAAAAAACAAAGUGGUAUUACAUUUGAGGAUGUUUCUAAAUAUUGUGUUUCAUCUUAAAGCAUAAUUAAAACAACCCUAAAGUAGUUCCCACUCUUAACUAUUCUAUUUCCAGUGAGAAAUCCAGGUAAACUGUAAAUAUUAUCAUUAGAUAGAAAAUCUAGGCCUGGGAAACAAAAUAAACUCCAUUUUUGUCACUCAUAUACCAAUUUCUAUAUACUUCAGUACCUUGACGAUCAGAAGCCAUCACUAAAUAUUUUAAAUAUGAUUCAUAAGUAAGUGAGAACAGUGAAUGAGCAAUAAUAGACUUUUCUUGCUUAUGUGAGUAAGACCAGAACAGAUAGUUCAUUCUCACUUGUCUCCUGAGGUCUUAUGAUUAGAAAAUACUAGAGGUGGAAAAAUGGAAGUACUCUAGCCUUUCACAAAGAAAAGACUUUCACAAGGAAAACACUUGCAGAAGUAGGAUAUCUGAGAUGUGCUUUAUUUAAAGAAAUGAGAUAGGGCAGUCUCUUUGUCUA